ACUUCCACGGCUCAGCGUCAGGCAAGUUGGCCUCUCUGUUGUAAAUUAGUGGUUAAGGUUAUCUAUUAUUGCCACUUUUCCAGCGCUAAAGGCUGUUUUGGAACCAGUGUUGCUUGUUCCGCGGGUGAUUGGCUUUUUUUUUUGGCAAACCAGUUAUUCAAGUUUCUGGUCUUUAAAAAACUCUGUGGCGGUACGGUAACCGAGGAGGUUCCAGCGCGGCGGAAGUACCCCGCGGGUGGGUGUGUGCGCAAGGCCAGGGCCAGAGGGGCACGUGGCGCCGGUGAGUGGCCGUAGAAGCCGGAGGAUUUGAAAAUGCUGGACGUGGAACCCAACUGCCGGAGGGAGGGAGGAAGGAAGGGGAUGCGGUGCGAAGACCUUGCUGUCUGUAGGGGGAGGAGAUACUAAUCAUGGGGCGGCAAGGGUGGUGUGUGGUCGGUCGGCGCUCACGAGACCAUGGAGAAGUAAACUCUUCACCCAUCAGGGAGGAGAGAGAAUGUCUUUUCGAGGCGGAGGUCGUGGAGGCUUUAAUCGAGGUGGUGGAGGUGGCGGCUUCAACCGAGGUGGCAGCAGCAACCACUUCCGAGGUGGAGGCGGCGGUGGAGGCGGCGGCAAUUUCAGAGGCGGCGGCAGGGGAGGAUUUGGACGAGGGGGUGGCCGCGGAGGCUUUAACAAAGGCCAAGACCAAGGACCUCCAGAACGUGUAGUCUUAUUAGGAGAGUUCCUGCAUCCCUGUGAAGAUGACAUAGUUUGUAAAUGUACCACAGAUGAAAAUAAGGUGCCUUAUUUCAAUGCUCCUGUUUACUUAGAAAACAAAGAACAAAUUGGAAAAGUGGAUGAAAUAUUUGGACAACUCAGAGAUUUUUAUUUUUCAGUUAAGUUGUCAGAAAACAUGAAGGCUUCAUCCUUUAAAAAACUACAGAAGUUUUAUAUAGACCCAUAUAAGCUGCUGCCACUGCAGAGGUUUUUACCUCGACCUCCAGGUGAGAAAGGACCUCCAAGAGGUGGUGGCAGGGGAGGCCGAGGAGGAGGAAGAGGAGGAGGUGGCAGAGGUGGUGGCAGAGGCGGUGGUUUUAGAGGUGGAAGAGGAGGUGGAGGUGGGGGCUUCAGAGGAGGAAGAGGUGGUGGUUUCAGAGGGAGAGGACAUUAAGUGAAACAGUUGACAGACAUCACCAGUUGACUUCUGCAUUAACCUGCAUGAUCUGUUUCUACUAUGGAUUGGAAACUUGUUUCUUGAACAAGUCUUGAAGAUCUUGGUCAUUUUAUGACAAUGGAUCUAAAAUGUCAGCAUCAUGCAAAGUGCAACGGAAUAGUGAAUUUUGCUCUAAAAGAGCAUGAACAAGUCUUUCUAAUGUUUUGUACAGUGCCUGGCACUCUGUGGGUGCUCAAUAAAUGGAUAGGAGUUUUCAUUUGAAGCAUAUUUGAAUUUUUAAAAUAAAGUGUUUUAUUCCCUUAA